UGAAUAAAUCACUUAGGCGAGAUAUAAAUUGGCUUUGUUCCAUAGCAGAUUUGCCUUUGUACUAGUUAAGAAAAUCCUGAAAAGCUUUCCCUGUAAGAGGAUCAGUUGGUUGGAAUAGCCUUGGUAGGAAGAAGCCAAGUUUGAUAAUUACUUGGUGAACGGAAAUGCUGGUUUCCAAAUGCUCAUCAGGGUUCAGUGGCACAAAGCUGGCUGUAGACUUGGCUUCUGUAGAUUUGGUAAAAACGUAAAUUCCUGGGGUCCCAGUGAUGCUGUUUUAGUCUGUACUGAUUUGCCCUGUGGCCACCCAGGAAUCUGUAUUUUUAAAAGUUUUCCAUGCUGAUUCUAAUGCAUAGCCAGGUUUAGUAACCAUUUAAUUCAGUAUUCAACUUAGAGACUUCAACCUUCUUGCACUGCAAAUUUGAUAAAUCUUUGUUUAUAUGAAUCUCCUUUGUUGAGUGCCAACUGGUUAUUUGCUGACUUUCUUUCAAUUCAGAAUUUGUUUUAGGUUCUGUUAUUGCAUAGAUUUGCAUACCUGUUUUAUGGUAUUUUAAUACUGUUGGUUUUAAAAAAUACCAUUUCCUCUGAGUGCUGUUCUGAAUAUAUUAUGUAAGCAAUUUUGUGUGUUCUUUUUUUUCCACUUGCAUAAAGCAGGGGAAAAGUUGAGAGUUUUUCUUAAUCCAGUUGCAAGUAGGACAAAGGAUAUGAGUGUUUAAAGAUCAUCUAUUAAAAUGCAUGAAAAAACACUAGAAAAUCUCCUGUGCACAUCGCCAGUCGUGUGUGUGCUCUAGAAGUGAAGUUCAGGGGGUAACAUAAUGGAGGAAUGUUUUCCUAGCUUCAUUCCCUGACGAUGUACAAGGUCUCUUCUCACAGGUUUGAAUCUUCAGACAAACUUCUGGGAGGACUCGGUCCCUGCCUCGCAGCAGAUGUUCCCUGUCACUCAGUAGCCAAUCCGGGGGACCCAGGACAUGCCCCAGCUAUAGUGAUGCAGAUUACCUUUCUGCUCCUGAAUCGCACCUGUGCCUCAGACUUUCUCCCCUCAGCUUGAGACUGCAUGUAAACUGGGAUGUGUGAAAGCAGGAAGCAAAGCUAGUGACAGCUGAGAGGUCCAUGUCUGGGUAGAACCAGGCCCACGAUGCUGCCUCUCCCGUGGUCUGGAGUUCAGCUGCAGGGACUCUGCUGAUGUGCCCAGCACCAUCGUUCUGUUUGUGCUUAAAUGGCACAGCAUUUGGUCAGCACAUCUGAAAAGGAAGGUGUGAGAAGCAAAGCCCAUGGCCACGUUCCCCUGCCAGUUAUGUGGCAAGACGUUCCUCACCCUGGAGAAGUUCACGAUUCACAAUUAUUCCCACUCCAGGGAGCGGCCGUACAAGUGUGUGCAGCCUGACUGUGGCAAAGCCUUUGUUUCCAGAUAUAAAUUGAUGAGGCAUAUGGCUACCCAUUCUCCCCAGAAAUCUCACCAGUGUGCUCACUGUGAGAAGACGUUCAACCGGAAAGACCACCUGAAAAACCACCUCCAGACCCACGACCCCAACAAAAUGGCCUUUGGGUGUGAGGAGUGUGGGAAGAAGUACAACACCAUGCUGGGCUAUAAGAGGCACCUGGCCCUCCAUGCGGCCAGCAGUGGGGACCUCACCUGUGGGGUCUGUGCCCUGGAGCUAGGGAGCACCGAGGUGCUACUGGACCACCUCAAAGCCCAUGCGGAAGAGAAGCCCCCUAGCGGAACCAAGGAAAAGAAGCACCAGUGCGACCACUGUGAAAGAUGCUUCUACACCCGGAAGGAUGUGCGACGCCACCUGGUGGUCCACACAGGAUGCAAGGACUUCCUGUGCCAGUUCUGUGCCCAGAGAUUUGGGCGCAAGGAUCACCUCACCCGGCAUACCAAGAAGACCCACUCACAGGAGCUGAUGAAAGAGAGCUUGCAGACCGGAGACCUUCUGAGCACCUUCCACACCAUCUCGCCUUCAUUCCAACUGAAGGCUGCUGCCUUGCCUCCUUUCCCUUUAGGAGCUUCUGCCCAGAACGGGCUUGCAAGUAGCUUGCCAGCUGAGGUCCAUAGCCUCACCCUCAGUCCCCCAGAACAAGCCGCCCAGCCUAUGCAGCCGCUGCCAGAGUCCCUGGCCUCCCUCCACCCCUCGGUAUCCCCUGGCUCUCCUCCGCCACCCCUUCCCAAUCACAAGUACAACACCACUUCUACCUCAUACUCCCCACUUGCAAGCCUGCCCCUCAAAGCAGAUACUAAAGGUUUUUGCAAUAUCAGUUUGUUUGAGGACUUGCCUCUGCAAGAGCCUCAGUCACCUCAAAAGCUCAACCCAGGUUUUGAUCUGGCUAAGGGAAAUGCUGGUAAAGUAAACCUGCCCAAGGAGCUGCCUGCAGAUGCUGUGAACCUAACAAUACCUGCCUCUCUGGACCUGUCCCCCCUGUUGGGCUUCUGGCAGCUGCCCCCUCCUGCUACCCAAAAUACCUUUGGGAAUAGCACUCUUGCCCUGGGGCCUGGGGAAUCUUUGCCCCACAGGUUAAGCUGUCUGGGGCAGCAGCAGCAAGAACCCCCACUUGCCAUGGGCACUGUGAGCCUGGGCCAGCUCCCCCUGCCCCCCAUCCCUCAUGUGUUCUCAGCUGGCACUGGCUCUGCCAUCCUGCCUCAUUUCCAUCAUGCAUUCAGAUAAUUGAUUUUUAAAGUGUAUUUUUCGUAUUCUGGAAGAUGUUUUAAGAAGCAUUUUAAAUGUCAGUUACAAUAUGAGAAAGAUUUGGAAAACGAGACUGGGACUAUGGCUUAUUCAGUGAUGACUGGCUUGAGAUGAUAAGAGAAUUCUCGAACUGCAUGUAUUGUGCCAAUCUGUCCUGAGUGUUCAUGCUUUGUACCAAAUUUAAUGAACGCGUGUUCUGUAAUCAAACUGCAAAUAUUGUCAUAACCAACAUCCAAAAUGACGGCUGCUAUAUAUAAGUGUUUGUCAUAUGGAAUUUAAUCGUAAGCCAUGAUCAUAAUGUUAACUAAAUAACUUUAUGUGGCACUGCCUAGUAAGGGAACUAUGGAAAGGUUUGGAUUUCUCCAAAUCUGGGAGAAUUUUCAAAAUAAGAAAAUAACCUUUAUAUGAUAUACUAUGACUAGGCUGUGUAUUUCUUUUCAGGGAUUUUUCUACCUUCAGGGUUGGAUGUAGUUUAGUUACUAUUACCAUAGCCAACCUGUAGUUUUACAUAUACAUUUUCUUGUGGAGCAAUAGAGUUCUCCAUUUUACAGAAGCAUUUUAAAUGUAGUUUGAAUAUUUUCCACAAGAUGCUGCAAUGUGAGUUAUCACUUCAUUUAUCUUAAAGAAAGACUAAACUGGUUGUCAGUUACAUCUGACAGAAAAAAAAAAAAAAUCACUGUGUAACCAGGUUAAGUGGUAAAAUAAUCCAGGCGUCAGUCAAAGGCAUUUUGCUGACUUUAAUAUUGAUUAUAUUUUUAACAGGAAUUUAAGAAAAUAUUACUGGAAUUAAAAAUAUAUAUAUAUUAAACAAGAAUUUUCUUUGCUCUGUCUAGCUUAAACUACUACUCAAGCUGCUUAAGUUCUUAAGUAUUGUUUGUAAUCACCAAUAAAUAAGUGCAUUUGUAAUUCAUCAGUCAUUAUUAGCUUUUAUUAAAAGAAGAUUACGUUUUACAAUGUAACUAUAAUCUCUUGAAUUUGGUAUCUUAUUAAUGAGUUUUAAAGAUGUAAAACCUAACCUUUUUUAAAGCUCCAUUGUCUUAUGUUUUUAGAGGCUUUUCCGUAAACAUAUAUCUUACAUAUAAUAAACUUUUCAAAUCUUGCAA